AAGUCCUCUCAGGCCAACCUCAGCGGGAGGCUCCUGGGAUCGGCUCCCUGCCCUUCCCACCUUAGGGUGUCCUCAGAGACAGACUUUUAUUCCCUCAGUAAGGAGACAGACUCUUAUUCUCUCAGCAGCCCAGCCCCUCACCUCCCCUCAGCCACAGCCACAUCAGUGGCCACCGUCUUCACCGUUGUCACCUCAGCCUAGUCGCCACUCCAGUUGAGGCACUGACUGGCGUCAUGUCUGCCACAGGGGAUCAAGACCUGAUCCAAGAGGACCAGGAGGCUCCAGUGAACCAGGAGGGAGCGCAGGCCGAGGCCGUAGGUGACCGGGAGGGCGGUGACUCUGGCCCCGACAGUGGCAACACUGUGGCCGGAGUCGCAGGGCCCAUGAGAGGCCUCGGGGAGGAGGAGGGUGAGCAGGCGGCAGGCUUGGCCGCAGCCCCCGGGGGUGGGAACGCCGAGGAAGACUCAGAGAUCAGGAUAGUAGUGGAGAUGGUGGAGGAGGAGGAGGAUGAGGAGGAGGAAGAGGAGGAGGAGGAGGAAGAGAGGAACGAGGCGGACAACUUCGACUUGGUCGCGGCCGCCCGUCGCUACCCCAUAAGAGGCUUUCGCAUGGAGUUUCUGGACAUGGUCCACUCCCUUCUCCUCCGCAUCUAUCACAACGACCACAUCCUGAUCAGGAUGCGUGGCGGCCGCCUGAUGCGGAGGCGCCGCACUGCGGCGCCCAGUGGCUCAGAAGAGCCCCGGCUGUUGCUGGUGCAUGAGAGGCUGGGCGUGGGGGCCGCGGGUCCUGAGGGCGAGGGCCUGGGCCUGCUCCAGGAGGCCGCGUUGGUCCCAGAGCCUGAGGUGCCAGCAGACCUGGCCGAGAUGGCCAGGGAGCCUGCAGAAGAGCCCGCAGAGGAGGCCUCAGAGAAGCCCACAGAGGAGGCCGCAGAAGAGCCCGCAGAGGAGGCCUCAGAGAAGCCCACAGAGGAGGCCGCAGAGGAGGAGCUCGCAGAGGAGGCCGCAGAGGAACCGGCCAAAGAGGAACCGGCUGCAGAGGAGGAGUCCGCAGAGGAACCGGCCACAGAGGAGGCUGCUGCCCCUGAGGAAGUCACUAAAUAUCAGCAUGAAAAGUGGGAUGAAGAGGCCCAAGAUGCUGCAGGCAAGGAAGAGAAAGAAGAGAAAGAGAAGGAUGCUGAAAACAAGGUGAAGAACUCCAAAGGGACCUAGACGCAGCAGAGGGGAAGCUGAGAAAAUCCAGUUGGGAAGAAUAGAAAGAAGAUGAAGAAAGAAGACUCUGUUGUUCAUUGUUUUUAUUUUAUUUUAUUCAGAUGCCUGUGAGAAUUUUAACACAUAUCAUUCCAAAGUUCAUUACCUUAAAAGUGAUAUCUAGUGACAUCUAACUUUUAUCUUUCACAAAUGUAUUUGACAGUGUUUGUUCAAGUUAGAAAUAAAAGUUUGUUUUAAAUGAAUAAAUUGAAACAUGGGGAGAUUUUUCAAUAAAUAAUUCUGACUCAAAUCUCUCUUUUACCUCUUUGUUUUGGCCCACCAUACCUUCAUUGAAAGGUAUUACUUUCCACCAUUUAGUAAGACUGUUUUAAAUUCUUUUACUGCAGCCAAAAGUCAAUUAAAAUGUCAAGUUUAAAACCAUUUUUGCAAAGAGAGAGAUGGGGCUCAAGUCUUUAGAGCUGUACUGUCUACUACCUUAGUCACUAGUAACGUUGUGGCUGCUGAGCACUUGUAAUAUGGCUAGUCUGUUUGAUAUGUGCUGUAAGUGUGAAAAUAAUAUUGCAUAUCUUACUAAUGAUUUUCAUACUGAUUACAUGUUGAGAUGAUAAUACUUGAAUUAAAAUGAAAUGUUAAAGUU